GUGCAGACCCGCGUGUGGCGCAGGCAAGGACCCUCAAAAUAAACAGCCUCUACCUUGCGAGCCGUCUUCCCCAGGCCUGCGUCCGAGUCUCCGCCGCUGCGGGCCCGCUCCGACGCGGAAGAUCUGACUGCAGCCAUGAGCAGCAAUGAGUGCUUCAAGUGUGGACGAUCUGGCCACUGGGCCCGGGAAUGUCCUACUGGUGGAGGCCGUGGUCGUGGAAUGAGAAGCCGUGGCAGAGGUGGUUUUACCUCGGAUAGAGGUUUCCAGUUUGUUUCCUCGUCUCUUCCAGACAUUUGUUAUCGCUGUGGUGAGUCUGGUCAUCUUGCCAAGGAUUGUGAUCUUCAGGAGGAUGUUGAAGCCUGCUAUAACUGCGGUAGAGGUGGCCACAUUGCCAAGGACUGCAAGGAGCCCAAGAGAGAGCGAGAGCAAUGCUGCUACAACUGUGGCAAACCAGGCCAUCUGGCUCGUGACUGCGACCAUGCAGAUGAGCAGAAAUGCUAUUCUUGUGGAGAAUUCGGACACAUUCAAAAAGACUGCACCAAAGUGAAGUGCUAUAGGUGUGGUGAAACUGGUCAUGUAGCCAUCAACUGCAGCAAGACAAGUGAAGUCAACUGUUACCGCUGUGGCGAGUCAGGGCACCUUGCACGGGAAUGCACAAUUGAGGCUACAGCCUAAUUAUUUUCCUUUGUCGCCCCUCCUUUUUCUGAUUGAUGGUUGUAUUAUUUUCUCUGAAUCCUCUUCACUGGCCAAAGGUUGGCAGAUAGAGGCAACUCCCAGGCCAGUGAGCUUUACUUGCCGUGUAAAAGGAGGAAAGGGGUGGAAAAAAACCGACUUUCUGCAUUUAACUACAAAAAAAGUUUAUGUUUAGUUUGGUAGAGGUGUUAUGUAUAAUGCUUUGUUAAAGAACCCCCUUUCCGUGCCACUGGUGAAUAGGGAUUGAUGAAUGGGAAGAGUUGAGUCAGACCAGUAAGCCCGUCCUGGGUUCCUUGAACAUGUUCCCAUGUAGGAGGUAAAACCAAUUCUGGAAGUGUCUAUGAACUUCCAUAAAUAACUUUAAUUUUAGUAUAAUGAUGGUCUUGGAUUGUCUGACCUCAGUAGCUAUUAAAUAACAUCAAGUAACAUCUGUAUCAGGCCCUACAUAGAACAUACAGUUGAGUGGGAGUAAACAAAAAGAUAAACAUGCGUGUUAAUGGCUGUUCGAGAGAAAUCGGAAUAAAAGCCUAAACAGGAACAACUUCAUCACAGUGUUGAUGUUGGACACAUAGAUGGUGAUGGCAAAGGUUUAGAACACAUUAUUUUCAAAGACUAAAUCUAAAACCCAGAGUAAACAUCAAUGCUCAGAGUUAGCAUAAUUUGGAGCUAUUCAGGAAUUGCAGAGAAAUGCAUUUUCACAGAAAUCAAGAUGUUAUUUUUGUAUACUAUAUCACUUAGACAACUGUGUUUCAUUUGCUGUAAUCAGUUUUUAAAAGUCAGAUGGAAAGAGCAACUGAAGUCCUAGAAAAUAGAAAUGUAAUUUUAAACUAUUCCAAUAAAGCUGGAGGAGGAAGGGGAGUUUGACUAAAGUUCUUUUUGUUUGUUUCAAAUUUUCAUUAAUGUAUAUAGUGCAAAAUACCAUAUUAAAGAGGGGAAUGUGGAGGACUGAAAGCUGACAGUUUGGACUUUUCUUUUUGUACUUAAGUCAUGUCUUCAAUAAUGAAAAUUGCUGUUAAAAGGAUGUAUGGGAUUUAGAUACUUUUGCAAAGCUAUAGAAAAUUCACUUUGUAAUCUGUUAUAAUAAUGCCCUUGAGUUCUGUGUUCAGUCUGAACAGGUUUUUUGGUGGUGGUGGUUUUGUUUUGUUUUGGAGACGGAGUCUCACUCUUGUCGCCCAGGCUGGAGUGCAGGCUUGGCUCACUGCAACCUCCACCUCCCGGGUUCAAGCAAUUCUCCUGCCUCAGCCUCCUGAGUAGCUGGGAUUACAGGCACCCGCCACCACCCCCCGCUAAUUUUUUGUAUUUUUAUUUUUAUUUUAUUUUUUUAUUUUUUUUUGAGACAGAGUGUCGCUCUGUUGCCCAGGCUGGAGUGUAGUGGUGCGAUCUCGGCUCACUGCAAGCUCCGCCUCCUGGGUUCGUGCCAUUCUCCUGCCUCAGCCUCCUGAGUAGCUGGGGCUACAGGUACCCGCCACCGCGCCCAGCUAAUUUUUUUUUUUUGUAUUUUUAGUAAAGACGGGGUUUCACGGUGUUAGCCAGGAUGGUCUCAAUCUCCUGACCUCGUGAUCCGCCCGCCUUGGCCUCCCAAAGUGCUGGGAUCACAGGCGUGAGCCACCGCGCCCGGCCUAUUUUUUGUAUUUUUAGUAGAGACUGGGUUUCAUCAUGUUGGUCGGGCUGGUCUCCAACUCCUGACCUCAGGUGAUCCACCUGCCCCGCCCCCCAAAGUGCUAGUGUUACAGGUGCGAGCCACCGUGUCUGGCCGAUUCUGAACAGUUUUAAUACCAUUGCUAUUUUUGUGUUUUUCCUGGGCCUUUUUUUUUUUUUUUUUUUUUUUUGAGACAGUCUCGCUCUGUUGCCCAGGCUAGAGUGCAAUGGUGCAAUCUCAGCUCACUGCAACCUCCACCCCCCACCCCCACACCCCGUUCAAGUAAUUCUCCUGCCUCAGCCUCCCAAAUAGCUGGGAUUACAGGUGUCCGCCACCACACCCAGCUAAUUUUUGUUAUUUUUAGUAGAGAUGGGGUUUCACUGUGUUGGUCAGGCUGGUCUCCAACUGUUGCCCUCAGGUGAGCCACUGUGCCCCACCUUUUCCUGGGUUUCAUAAGGAUCUGAAGUGGUGGAUUCCUUGUUUUUGCUAGUGUCUCAUUUAGAGUUGAGAUGGACCUUAAAACUCAUCUGUUUUAACUCACUUUUUAAUAGAUGAGUUAAACUUAAUUUACUUAAGGAUGUACAGUUAGAGCCUGGAACUUCAACCAUUAUUCACUCCCCAUGCCCUGUUUCCCCCCACUUCGAAAUUAAAUGCGGUUAGCAUCAUAUAGUUCAUUUUCCCCCUCCAUGCUGCUGUGUGAUUCUUGACUUUGGGUAUGAGUUUUUCAUCCUUCAUGCAGGGUUCUGUCAGUUCAUGGUAUAGUGAUUCAGUGUUAAAAUGGUGGUGUCUCAGCUGUGCUGUGCACAUUCCAACCUUGUCAAAUUAAUAGUCCUGAGCAAGCAAGAAAAAGAGGUAAUAACAUACCCAUUUCUUUAUGAAUAUAAGCUUAUAAUAUUUUUUCAUGUGCUAUUUUUACUGAGCAAAUUGUAUGUCUCACAUGUUAACACAAUAAAUAUCUUGACAAUUUUA